CGUGAAUGGGAGUCAUCCUGGGAAUCCCGGACCGGCCCUGGGCCUGAGACACCCCUCUCCCGCUGCUCUGCCCCUUACCCCACAGUCUUGCCUUGGCCCUUUCAGCUGCUGAAAGCUUUGAAUUCCUUUAUUGGUGCAGAAGGGAAGCUGGGGAGCCCUGAGGGGUGGAAAGAAAGGGGACUUGAGUGUGUUUGGGCAGAGUGAGAUUCUUGGGUUUGCUGGGGUCAGGGGCAUGUGGUGAAGGCAGCCCCCAGCCCCCUAGAGGAGGGGCCUUGGUAGGGUUAAAAGUGAGAGGGAGACUACUUCAGCCAGCUCCGCACCCAUCUCUGAGGCAGGAGGCCUUUUGAUCCUCCUCUCUAUCAGCCACCUCUGGCCCAGGAAGUUCUUCCUCAGAGCUGACUUUAGUACCUCUCCUAUCUAACUCUUGUGCAGGGAUGGGUCUGUGGUCUUCCUGGGUUUGGAGGUAGCCAGCCACUUAUGGUUCAACCCAAAGAGCCUUCCCAGAGGCAGUGCCCUGUACCUCAGCAGGCAAGAGGGCAGCGUUUAUGAGGUCCUGAAAAGACAGAGAGGAGACAGGGCUGUGAGCUAGGCUCUGUGCUGGGAACUUGUUGGGAGGCUGAUGAGGUGUCUGCCAUCCCCAGGGCAAGGCUCAUGGUCUGCAUUGCACAGAGAGGGAAACAGGCUCAGGGGGGUUAAUCAUGACUAAGAGCCACUUGGGCUGCCUGUGAGGCAAGGAUCAUCCUUCUAGGUCCCCUUCCCGGGUGGCUCAGGGAGAGGCCUCUGGGUCAUCAGUGCCCCCAGGAGGACAGGCCUGGCUAUACACAGGCAGGAGGGUCUUCAAUGAACCAGUGGCUGUCUGUGACCCAGCUUGGAAUUGGGUCUUUGCCUUAUUUUGAAUGGUGGGAAGUAAUAUAAAAAGGCGCCCCAAAAGGUCUUAUGUCAUAGCCGGCACAGUGAGGGUUACGCAUGUCCAGGACGAAAUCCCAGAAUGAGCGUGAAGGUGUCUGAAGGAGACUGAGGGGAGGAGGGGGGUUGGAUUGGGUUAAAAGUGACUCCAUUCUGGAGAAGCCAGCCUGUGGCUCUGAAGGAUGUGGACCUUGUGCUUCUUGAUGGGGCGGGGCUGUGGAGUAGGGAGCAGCAGCCUAGGAGCAGGGUAGGGGAGGGAGAUCCAGCUUCAGACAUGCAAAGGAAGACCCCGCAGAGGAUCCUGCCUGACACUUAGCUGUCAUAUGCUGAGCCUCAGAGGGCCAGAUACUCAUGUGUGUUCUCAGUCGAGAAUGCGUGUGCACCUCUGUGCAUGUGUACAAGUGUAAGCCUCUACACCCCUGUGUGUGCGUGUUAACUCCUGAGUGUGUGUGACAGCAUGAAUCUGUGGGUUUCACCUGUGUGCAUGUCCGUGUACAUAUGUAUCCAUUCAUAUGCAGAACUCCUGUGAACAUCUGUGCCCUCAUGCUUUGGUGUGUGUGUCCUCAGGGCACAAGGGUGUUCAAACCCAUGUGUGUUGGUGUGUAUGUGAGGGGAGGUUCCCUGAGCUGCUGUAAGUGGGGGAGGGGAGGCCGGUUAUAAUGAGCCCCUACCUCCCCUCCACUGAGCCGCAGCCAUGGCCUGAAUUUUGCGGCUUAAAAAUAAUUGGGGGCAGCAGGGGGAUUGGAUGUCACUCAUCAUCAGCCGCUGGCUUGGCUAGUGCCGCAGCAGGUGGGGCGAGCUGAGCAGUGUGGGACAGGCAUGAUGUAGGGUGGGAAAGACCAGGGGUCUGAUCCCUUUUUCAGCUCUGAGGAGGAGGGUGGGUGGUUGGGGGGAGAGGCACAGCCUGUCUGGCUUCCGCCGAAUAACUCCAUGUGGGUCUUGGGAGGAGGGUGGGGUGGCUCCUCUGCAGUGAGUAGGUCUGCCUGGAGCUACUCCACCAUCUCCCCCAGCCCCUGUAUGGCUGGGAGGGGAAGAUGCUUGCUUGGGCCUGGCUUGGAGGUGCAGCAUGAAGGGAUGUGGGAUCUGGAGCAGUGGGGAGCUCCAUGGAUGCUGCACAGGGACUGGAAAGUUGGGGUUCUAAAUUCUGUCCCCCCUCUGCCUGCUGUUUAGACUCCUGAAGACCCAAGGGGAAGUCUGUUCCCUGGGAGCAACUGUGUCUUGGGAGAAUCUAGUCAUACCUGUGAAUUGUCCUGUGUUUCUGAUUCAGUCCCCAGAGCUAAUAGCUGGUCCAUCUGGCCUGAAGCCUGAGCAGCAAGCCUAGGGAAGGAGCAGAGGCUACUGGUGGAGGGAGACAGGCCUGGGCUGGGCCUCAGAUCCUGGGCUUGCGUCCUCUGUGGCCACCUUUGUGUGAUCUGGAGCGGGUUGUCUCCCUUUUCCUAGCCCCAUCUUUUCUCCUCUGAUGAGGACCAGCUGGGCUCUAGGGGGCCCAUGCAGUGCUGUGAGCUAUCCUGUGGCAUGCAGGAGGGAGGCCGCUUGGAUUACUUGGGGGGUAGGAUUGGAAGUGGGGCUGAUUCAGACCACGCGCUAGGUUCCAUUUUCUGGGCAGUUGGGUAGAGGUUGCGCAGGCUGUGGGCAGUGACACAGCCCUGGCCUGGUGGGUGGGAGGGCACCUGCAGCUCCCCCCAUCCUCAGCCCUUACCCACUCUGGCCUGACUGCUCUGUGUGUCUGUAUGGGUCGGGCUUGGGUCCUAGGUGCCCACCCACACCUGGAGUACAUUCACACCUGUUGGGAGCUCAGCUUAGGGCAGCACUUUAAGGGAAGGUAGAAAGCAACAAGCUUGGGUCCCCACUCUUAGGAACUGGAAGACCCAUAAGCUGAAUGAACUAGCCUUGGGGAAACAGUAUAGGAGAGAGGUCACGACUGGCUGGUGGCUUCACAGGUGGGUAGUGGGGGGUGGGGUAGCAGGCCCUGAACCAGGCCUUGGAAGAUAAUCCCAUGGAGCUGGAGGGGAAGAGGGAAGUAAGAGGGGGAAUUUCUGCACCCAUUUUACAGAUGAGAAAACUGAGACUCAUGAGGGUCACCCACCAGCAGGUGGCUGGCUGGGUUGGGGCUCAAGCCCAAUGUCCCCUUACUCGGUGCCUCUCCCCCUUAUUCCAACCAGGAAAUCCACAGCAGUGAUACAUGUGACGUCCACACUGACAGUGCCCUCCUGUGGGCAUGGCUCAGGUUGUGCGCAGUUCCUGGCACACUGGCUGUAACUCCGCCCCUUUCUCUCCCUCUCAGUAAAGCAAGUGAGUGAGAAUGACAUUGUUCCAGGAAUAACCUCAAAUUGCUCUAAUUUAUAAAAAAGCAAAUCAUAGUCAAACAUCACCACUUUGACAAUUACCACAGGAUUACGCGGUGACAUGCCUCACAGCUGAUCACGACACACGGGGAUGGAGAGCAAGAGUUAUGGAGAAUACAGGUUGGAUGGUGAGGCUGGGGCUGGAUCUGAAUGCAAGGCGAAUAUGCUUGUAGUUGAUGGGCUGACUCUGAGGAAACAGAACGAUGGCAACAACAACUACUGUUUCUUCAGGGCUCACAAGAUUCCAGGCACUCUCGCGAGUCCUUUCCCUUACUUAUUUCACCCUUGUAGGAAACUUGUGCGAUAGGUCCUAUCAUUGGUCCAUUUUACAGGUAAGGAAACUGAGGCUCAGAGAGGUCAAGUCCCUUGUCUAAGUUCACACAGGUGGACCCAGGUGACACUUCAAAGACCAGGGUCUUAACUUAUGAGGCCCACUCCCGCAGCUCACCAUAGAAGGUUCAGAGCCCAUGCUGGCUGUGCUGGGGGCCCGCUGACCACUGUCUCUCUCCACAGGGCAAGGGACAUAGGAUGACCCCAGCCUGUCCCCUCUUACUGUCUGUGAUUCUGUCCCUGCGCCUGGCCACCGCCUUCGACCCCGCCCCCAGUGCCUGCUCUGCCCUGGCCUCGGGUGUGCUCUACGGGGCCUUCUCGCUGCAGGACCUCUUUCCUACCAUCGCCUCGGGCUGCUCCUGGACCCUGGAGAACCCUGACCCCACCAAGUACUCCCUCUACCUGCGCUUCAACCGCCAGGAGCAGGUGUGCGCACACUUUGCCCCCCGCCUGCUGCCCCUGGACCACUACCUGGUCAACUUUACCUGCCUGCGGCCUAGCCCCGAGGAGGCGGUGGCCCAGGCGGAGUCAGAGGUGGGGCGGCCAGAAGAGGAGGAGGCAGAGGCGGCAGCGGGGUUGGAGCUGUGCAGCGGCUCAGGCCCCUUUACCUUCCUGCACUUCGACAAGAACUUCGUGCAGCUGUGCCUGUCGGCUGAGCCCUCCGAGGCCCCGCGCCUGCUGGCGCCCGCUGCCCUAGCCUUCCGCUUUGUCGAGGUCUUGCUCAUCAACAACAACAACUCUAGCCAAUUCACCUGUGGUGUGCUCUGCCGCUGGAGUGAGGAGUGUGGCCGCGCUGCCGGCAGGGCCUGCGGCUUUGCUCAGCCAGGCUGCAGCUGCCCUGGAGAGGCGGGGGCCGGCUCCACCACCACCACAUCUCCAGGCCCUCCUGCUGCCCACACCCUGUCCAAUGCCCUGGUGCCCGGGGGCCCAGCCCCACCUGCUGAGGCCGAUUUGCACUCGGGGAGCAGCAAUGAUCUGUUCACAACCGAGAUGAGAUAUGGUGAGGAGCCGGAAGAGGAACCGAAAGUGAAAACCCAGUGGCCGAGGUCUGCAGAUGAGCCUGGGCUAUACAUGGCGCAGACAGGCGACCCGGCGGCUGAGGAGUGGUCCCCGUGGAGCGUGUGUUCCCUGACGUGUGGGCAGGGUCUGCAGGUGCGGACCCGCUCCUGUGUGUCCUCCCCCUAUGGGACCCUGUGCAGCGGGCCCCUGCGGGAGACCAGGCCCUGCAACAAUUCAGCCACCUGCCCAGUGGAAGGCCAGUGGUUAGAAUGGGGUCCCUGGGGCCCAUGCUCCACGUCCUGUGCCAAUGGGACCCAACAGCGCAGCCGGAAGUGCAGCGUGGCGGGCCCAGCCUGGGCCACAUGCACGGGUGCCCUCACUGACACCCGGGAGUGCAGCAACCUCGAGUGCCCGGCCACUGAUAGCAAGUGGGGGCCAUGGAAUGCGUGGAGCCUGUGCUCUAAGACGUGUGACACAGGCUGGCAGCGCCGCUUCCGCAUGUGCCAGGCCACGGGCACGCAGGGCUACCCCUGCGAGGGCACCGGAGAGGAGGUGAAGCCUUGUAGUGAGAAGAGGUGUCCAGCCUUCCAUGAGAUGUGCAGGGAUGAGUACGUGAUGCUGAUGACGUGGAAGAAGGCAGCUGCUGGCGAGAUCAUCUACAACAAGUGCCCCCCGAAUGCCUCAGGGUCUGCCAGCCGCCGCUGUCUCCUCAGUGCCCAAGGCGUGGCGUACUGGGGGCUGCCCAGCUUUGCUCGCUGCAUCUCCCAUGAGUACCGCUACCUGUAUCUGUCACUUAGGGAGCACCUGGCCAAGGGGCAGCGCAUGCUGGCAGGCGAGGGCAUGUCGCAGGUGGUGCGCAGCCUGCAGGAGCUACUGGCCCGGCGCACCUACUAUAGUGGGGACCUGCUCUUCUCUGUGGACAUUCUGAGGAAUGUCACUGACACCUUUAAGAGGGCCACCUACGUGCCCUCGGCUGAUGAUGUGCAGCGCUUCUUCCAGGUGGUGAGCUUCAUGGUGGAUGCGGAAAACAAGGAGAAGUGGGACGAUGCUCAGCAGGUGUCCCCUGGCUCUGUGCACCUGCUCCGUGUCGUGGAGGACUUCAUUCACCUGGUGGGCGAUGCUCUCAAGGCCUUCCAGAGCUCUCUGAUUGUCACAGAUAAUCUAGUGAUCAGCAUUCAGCGAGAGCCCGUCUCAGCUGUGUCCAGUGACAUCACGUUCCCCAUGCGGGGCCGCCGGGGCAUGAAGGACUGGGUGCGGCACUCAGAGGACCGCCUCUUCCUGCCCAAGGAGGUGCUCAGCCUCUCCUCCCCAGGGAAGCCAGCCACAUCUGGGGCAGCAGGCAGCCCUGGCAGGGGGAGGGGCCCAGGAACGGUGCCUCCUGGCCCAGGCCACUCCCACCAGCGCCUCCUCCCAGCAGACCCUGAUGAGUCCUCCUACUUUGUGAUCGGUGCUGUACUCUACCGCACCCUUGGCCUCAUCCUGCCGCCUCCCAGGCCCCCGCUGGCCGUCACAUCCCGGGUGAUGACAGUGACUGUGCGCCCCCCUACCCAGCCUCCAGCUGAGCCCCUCAUCACUGUGGAGCUCUCCUACAUCAUCAAUGGGACCACGGAUCCCCAUUGCGCCAGCUGGGACUACUCCAGAGCAGAUGCCAGCUCAGGAGACUGGGACACUGAAAAUUGCCAGACCCUGGAGACCCAGGCAGCUCACACCCGCUGCCAGUGCCAGCACCUGUCCACCUUUGCUGUACUAGCCCAGCCGCCCAAGGACCUGACCCUGGAGCUGGCGGGCUCCCCCUCGGUCCCCCUGGUGAUCGGCUGUGCAGUGUCGUGCAUGGCGCUGCUCACCCUGCUCGCCAUCUAUGCCGCCUUUUGGAGGUUCAUAAAAUCUGAACGCUCCAUCAUCUUGCUGAACUUCUGCCUGUCCAUCUUGGCAUCCAACAUCCUGAUCCUCGUGGGCCAGUCCCGGGUGCUGAGCAAGGGCGUGUGCACCAUGACGGCUGCCUUCCUGCACUUCUUCUUUCUCUCCUCCUUUUGCUGGGUGCUUACCGAGGCCUGGCAGUCCUACCUGGCUGUCAUUGGGCGGAUGCGCACCCGCCUCGUUCGCAAGCGCUUCCUCUGCCUGGGCUGGGGUCUGCCUGCCCUGGUGGUGGCCGUGUCUGUUGGCUUUACCCGAACGAAAGGAUACGGUACAUCCAGCUACUGCUGGCUCUCCCUGGAGGGCGGCCUGCUCUACGCCUUUGUGGGCCCUGCAGCCGUCAUUGUCCUGGUGAACAUGCUCAUCGGAAUCAUCGUCUUCAACAAGCUCAUGGCACGUGAUGGCAUCUCCGACAAAUCCAAGAAGCAGAGGGCCGGGGCCUCACUCUGGAGCUCCUGCGUGGUGCUGCCCCUGCUGGCGCUCACCUGGAUGUCUGCCGUCCUGGCUAUGACAGACCGCCGUUCCGUCCUCUUCCAGGCCCUCUUUGCUGUCUUCAACUCCGCGCAGGGCUUUGUCAUCACUGCUGUGCACUGCUUCCUGCGCCGAGAGGUCCAGGAUGUGGUGAAGUGCCAGAUGGGGGUGUGCCGGGCUGAUGAGAGCGAAGACUCCCCUGACUCGUGUAAGAACGGGCAGCUGCAGAUCCUGUCAGACUUUGAAAAGGAUGUGGAUCUGGCUUGUCAAACAGUGCUGUUCAAGGAGGUCAACACUUGCAACCCGUCCACCAUCACGGGCACACUAUCCCGCCUGUCCCUGGAUGAGGAUGAGGAGCCCAAGUCCUGCCUCGUGGGCCCUGAGGGCAGCCUCAGCUUCUCACCACUGCCUGGGAAUAUCCUGGUGCCCAUGGCAGCCUCACCAGGGCUGGGGGAGCCUCCGCCCCCACAGGAGGCCAACCCUGUUUACAUGUGUGGGGAGGGUGGCCUGCGGCAGCUGGACCUCACAUGGCUGCGGCCCACUGAGCCAGGCUCUGAGGGAGACUACAUGGUGCUGCCCCGGCGGACUUUGAGCCUGCAGCCUGGCGGUGGGGGUGGAGGUGGUGAGGAUGCCCCCAGGGCCCGGCCGGAGGGGACCCCCCGGCGAGCUGCCAAGACAGUGGCCCACACUGAAGGCUACCCCAGCUUCCUGUCCGUGGACCACUCGGGCCUGGGGCUGGGCCCUGCCUAUGGAUCUCUCCAGAAUCCCUAUGGAAUGACCUUCCAACCGCCACCGCCGACACCCAGCGCCCGCCAAGUGCCCGAGCCAGGGGAGCGCAGCCGGACCAUGCCUCGCACCGUGCCCGGCUCUACCAUGAAGAUGGGCUCCCUGGAGCGAAAGAAAUUACGGUAUUCAGACCUGGACUUUGAGAAGGUGAUGCACACCCGGAAACGGCAUUCAGAACUCUACCACGAGCUCAACCAGAAGUUCCACACUUUCGACCGCUACCGCAGCCAGUCCACGGCCAAGGAUAAGCCCAGCCCUGGGGAGCGCCCCAGCUUGUCCCAACAUCGGCGCCAUCAGAGCUGGAGCACCUUCAAAUCUAUGACACUGGGCUCGCUGCCCCCCAAGCCCCGAGAACGGCUGACUCUGCACCGGGCAGCAGCCUGGGAGCCCACAGAACCACCGGAUGGUGACUUCCAGACAGAGGUGUGAGUGCCACGCUGGACUGCCCACUGCAUAUAAAUAUAUAUAUCUCUCUAUUUUCACACUCCACUUUGGAACUACCCAGGAGCCAGCGCCCUCUCCCCUCUCCCGAGGGCUGGGCAGGGAGGCGCCGUGGACUCAGCCAGGCUGGGGGAGCCGGACAUGGCUUGGCCUGGGGUCCCAGGGCCCUUCCUUGUUUCUCAGAGGCCCCUCAGCCACUGGAACCCCAUCUUCAGCCCAGCCUGUCCGUCCCUGUCCCGGGCUGGGGAGGGGGGAGGGGAACUUUGUUGGGAAUAAACUUCACUCUGUGGA